GCUCCGCGGGAGCGGCCCGCAGCUCGGGAGCUUGGGGUAGCUUUGUGAAUGCGUGGCUCCCUGGAAAUCCCGAGGCUGGUCUCCGCAGCAUCUAGGUAGAGAGGGAAAGUUUGGCCUGAGAAAGUUUGAGUGGUGGGCGCUCGCAGAGCGUGAGUUGGGAUGGGGCAAGGGAUGUGGAUUUUCACCGUAGGGGUGGAGUAGCCAGGAUGGGAGACGCCACUGAAAGGCAGAGCGCAGGAGUUGGCGAGGGAGGGUCCUGGCUGUCACAGUUGGACGCGCGAACGGCAGCGUCUGGGCGACAGGCGAUGUCCCAGCCACUGAAACCGUAUUUGGGGGCACUUUCAAAAUAGAUCAGGAGAAAAUAAAAACAAUUUGAUUUUUGAUUUUUAGAGAUACCAAAAUCACAACUUGAUUUUUGGAGGAAUUAAAGCAACCUGCGAUGUCAAGGCUACGUAGGUUGAACUUUGCAGGUUGACCGUGUGUGACUUGGCUAACGCAAGAGUGAGUGACAGAUGUAAGCAUCGGAAAGGGCAUCAUUUCUUUGACUGCUUGUUCUCAAGUCUGGAAGAGAUCGGCGUCGUAAUCACAGAAGCCAGACCUCCACUUUCCUGUGACAGAGGGAGAUUACCGAGGCAUUUUAGAGCCAAGGCGGGUCAAAUGAUAAUUGCUUCUAAUUGGCAUCCCCAGAAGCACCUUAAUUAUUUAUCUGCAGCUGUCACUCAAAGAGGGAAAUUCUUCCUACCUUUGGAAAACUGGUUUUCUUUCAUAUUGUUAUUCUAAUACAUACAAAGCAAAGCACAAAAUCUGCAAGAGCAAAGAUAUUUACACGAAAGCAAAGGUUUAAGUAUCUGAUCAUUAAAGUGUUGUUGUGCCGUCUUUAAAAAUGAGGUCUGAAAAACAGAAGCUAUCACGUGAAAGGUGAAACCCGUAAAGAAGGGGUGAAAAUGAGGGGGACAGGUAAUUCAGAAAUAAGAUCCAGAAGUGAGAAGGUGAGGUAAUAGCAACCUGGUGUGUGCAGCAUUUCUAAAAUGAAAGAGAACAAAUAACAGGAACCUGGGGAAUUUGAGAACACAAAGAAGCAUAGUAUCCAUGAAUUAUGAAGAGAAACAGAUACAAACUAGAAAGGAUUGUAAAAAUUAUGUGACCAAAUAAUACUUUGAUUGAACCUUCAAUAUAAAAAUAUAUUUUCAUUAGUAAAUCCAAGGUGCAUUGCAGCUUCUGGAGAUUUAAGCUUAGCCUAAAGUCUGAGACACACCUACAGUUUCAUUUUCAAAGUAAAACAUUCACCUAGUAAUAAAAUGAGUUUUAAUUUUCCUAUCAGUGGCAUAUUUAGGGCAUAUUUUUGGAAGAUUAGUAUGCAAAACAUCAAGUUUGUCAAUUUUUUCCUGUUGCAAUAUAUGACUAACUGAAGUUUUGAAACAGUAAGAUAACUUCUAUUUAUUUUAAAGUUUGCACCUAGAGACAAGAGUUUGACGUAUGACGACUGCACAUCUGUUUGAUAGUGGUGCUUAACAUAACCCUGAUUUGAAAAAGUGGCAUUAUUUUGUUCAGUGUGCCUGACAGGAGGGAGAAGGAAAGCUAUUUGAGAUUAGUUGACUUUAAAAUAUAUGAGUGGAACUAGGAAAUGCUAAUAUCUAACUUCUCAGCCCAACUGCCGGCAAAGUACUAGCUCUGUGAUUAGAUUGAAUUCUCCAACAACAACAUCUCAGAUUAUGGCAAGAAAGAAAAGGAGAGGGAUUAUAGAGAAAAGGCGUCGGGAUCGGAUAAAUAACAGUUUAUCUGAGUUGAGAAGACUUGUGCCAACUGCUUUUGAAAAACAAGGAUCUGCAAAGUUAGAAAAAGCUGAAAUAUUGCAAAUGACAGUGGAUCAUUUGAAGAUGCUUCAGGCAACAGGGGGUAAAGGCUACUUUGACGCACACGCUCUUGCCAUGGACUUCAUGAGCAUAGGAUUCCGAGAGUGCCUAACAGAAGUUGCGCGGUACCUGAGCUCCGUGGAAGGCCUGGACUCCUCGGAUCCGCUGCGGGUGCGGCUUGUGUCUCAUCUCAGCACUUGCGCCACCCAGCGGGAGGCGGCGGCCAUGACAUCCUCCAUGGCCCACCACCAUCAUCCGCUCCACCCGCAUCACUGGGCCGCCGCCUUCCACCACCUGCCCGCAGCCCUGCUCCAGCCCAACGGCCUCCAUGCCUCAGAGUCAACCCCUUGUCGCCUCUCCACAACUUCAGAAGUGCCUCCUGCCCACGGCUCUGCUCUCCUCACGGCCACGUUUGCCCAUGCGGAUUCAGCCCUCCGAAUGCCAUCCACGGGCAGCGUCGCCCCCUGCGUGCCACCUCUCUCCACCUCUCUCUUGUCCCUCUCUGCCACCGUCCACGCCGCAGCCGCAGCAGCCACCGCGGCUGCACACAGCUUCCCUCUGUCCUUCGCGGGGGCAUUCCCCAUGCUUCCCCCAAACGCAGCAGCAGCAGUGGCCGCGGCCACAGCCAUCAGCCCGCCCUUGUCAGUAUCAGCCACGUCCAGUCCUCAGCAGACCAGCAGUGGAACAAACAAUAAACCUUACCGACCCUGGGGGACAGAAGUUGGAGCUUUUUAAAUUUUUCUUGAACUUCUUGCAAUAGUAACUGAAUGUCCUCCAUUUCAGAGUCAGCUUAAAACCUCUGCACCCUGAAGGUAGCCAUACAGAUGCCGACAGAUCCACAAAGGAACAAUAAAGCUAUUUGAGACACAAACCUCACGAGUGGAAAUGUGGUAUUCUCUUUUUUUUCUCUCCCUUUUUUGUUUGGUUCAAGGCAGCUCGGUAACUGACAUCAGCAACUUUUGAAAACUUCACACUUGUUACCAUUUAGAAGUUUCCUGGAAAAUAUAUGGACCGUACCAUCCAGCAGUGCAUCAGUAUGUCUGAAUUGGGGAAGUAAAAUGCCCUGACUGAAUUCUCUUGAGACUAGAUGGGACAUACAUAUAUAGAGAGAGAGUGAGAGAGUCGUGUUUCGUAAGUGCCUGAGCUUAGGAAGUUUUCUUCUGGAUAUAUAACAUUGCACAAGGGAAGACGAGUGUGGAGGAUAGGUUAAGAAAGGAAAGGGACAGAAGUCUUGCAAUAGGCUGCAGACAUUUUAAUACCAUGCCAGAGAAGAGUAUUCUGCUGAAACCAACAGGUUUUACUGGUCAAAAUGACUGCUGAAAAUAAUUUUCAAGUUGAAAGAUCUAGUUUUAUCUUAGUUUGCCUUCUUUGUACAGACAUGCCAAGAGGUGACAUUUAGCAGUGCAUUGGUAUAAGCAAUUAUUUCAUCAGUUCUCAGAUUAACAAGCAUUUCUGCUCUGCCUGCAGGCCCCCAGGCACUUUUUUUUUUGGAUGGCUCAAAAUAUGGUGCUGCUUUAUAUAAACCUUACAUUUAUAUAGUGCACCUAUGAGCAGUUGCCUACCAUGUGUCCACCAGAGGCUAUUUAAUUCAUGCCAACUUGAAAACUCUCCAGUUUGUAGGAGUUUGGUUUAAUUUAUUCAGUUUCAUUAGGACUAUUUUUAUAUAUUUAUCCUCUUCAUUUUCUCCUAAUGAUGCAACAUCUAUUCUUGUCACCCUUUGGGAGAAGUUACAUUUCUGGAGGUGAUGAAGCAAGGAGGGAGCACUAGGAAGAGAAAAGCUACAAUUUUUAAAGCUCUUUGUCAAGUUAGUGAUUGCAUUUGAUCCCAAAACAAGAUGAAUGUAUGCAAUGGGAUGUACAUAAGUUAUUUUUGCCCAUGCCUAAACUAGUGCUAUGUAAUGGGGUUGUGGUUUUGUUUUUUUCGAUUUCGUUUAAUGACAAAAUAAUCUCUUAAUAUGCUGAAAUCAAGCACGUGAGAGUUUUUGUUUAAAAGAUAAGAGACACAGCAUGUAUUAUGCACUUCAUUUCUCUACUGUGUGGAGAAAGCAAUAAACAUUAUGAGAAUGUUAAACGUUAUGCAAAAUUAUACUUUUAAAUAUUUGUUUUGAAAUUACUGUACCUAGUCUUUUUUGCAUUACUUUGUAACCUUUUUCUAUGCAAGAGUCUUUACAUACCACUAAUUAAAUGAAGUCCUUUUUGACUA